UUUAAUUCAGCAUCUUACUGUUCACAGUGUCUAGCACCCUGUCUUGCUCAUGCGUAGCAGGAGCUUAACAAACACUCCAUGCAAACAACCUCUGACAACAGUGGAUUCCUGAUUCCUUCAGUGGGAAGAACCACAGCUGUCAAGCUUCCCCUUAGGAUGCAGAAACCCAAUUACUCUUUCCUUUGCUUCUUUCUUCAGUUGGGUUCUUUGAGUUGGACUCAAAUUGAGCCAGGUAGCACAGAAGAGCAGGGGAGGCACAUUCGGGGACCAUUGCUCCCCUGACCAUGGAUACUUCUAUGGAUGAUUGGCAGGCUCCACGAUCUGGAGGGAGCGUGACCCCUCCAUGCACUGGGCCCACUCAGAGCACGCCCUCAGUGCAGGGAUUAUCUGUGGACAUCAAACCUUGUCAGUGGUGGUAGCCCUUGCUUUCUGUCAGUGCUCAGCAACGGGGGCUCUCCUGGGGCUCUGGGCUUUUGUAGAGCACCCUGUCUUCCUGUCAUUCCCUUCUUCUCCCCCGGGGUAGGGCUGCUGUUUCCACAGAGGCACUCGUGUCUCUAAACUGUGUCCCAGCUGAGUCCCAGGGGCCUCCAUUCCUGAGCUAUCACGGCAGGCAGGCUUCUCUUCUGGAAGGGAAAUAAUAGUAACAGCCAGUGCUUACAUGGCUCUUACAGUGUCCCAGGCUUUGUGCCAAGUGCUUUAUAUUUACUAACUCCUAAACCCUCACCACCCCCCUAUGAUGUAGAUUUUGUCAUCUCCAAAUAGAGAGGAGGUAACCAAGACACAGAGCUGAAAUAACUUGCCUAAAGCCAUGCAGCUAGAAAGAGGUCUAGCUGAGACUGGAGCCUGGGCAGUCUGGCUCCUGAGUCCACGCAUUUAACUCCCACAUCAAACAUUCCUCUUGAGAAUGGGAGCAGUGGUGAAGUCUGGCCUUUCUUCCUCUUCUGUCUCCAUUUAAGCCCUGGAUGAGAGAGAGUCUUUCUUUUUACUGCUUGAUUCUGUGGACCACCUCCCAUCCUUCCUUAGCCUGUUUUUUUGUUGUGGCCUGGAGCCACGCUCUGGCAGGUGCUUGCAUUUGAGUGAAUGUGUAUGUGUGUAGACUUGAUUACACUUCAUCACAUGGAUGCCCGGGUCCCCCAAGUAGGGUCCCCUAAGAUGGGGUGGCAGUGGGGGGAGGUGCUAGAGGACUCAGUGGUGGGUGCUCAGAAGAAGCGAAUGACGGCAGAGCCAGGGAAUCAAGAAGGGCACACACAUCUUGAAAGUAACUUUCCACUCACCUACCCCACCCCCACUGCUCCUUUCCUUGCCUUCUAAUCUGAUCUUGGUAUUUAUGGAGAUGCUAAACAGAUCAUGUCCUCUGAGGAUGGAGAAGGGGAAGACCCUAUGGCCCUGUUGAUCUCAUUACUCUAUGUCUUCUCAGCAGAUCUGCCGCCCUGCUGCUCAUUCAGGCUUGGGGCUAAUCAUAUUAAUUGAAAUAUUAAACAUUCACAAAAAUGAAUUAAAAUGAACUCCCCUCACUCCUCCUCCCAGUCAGUAAUUGGGGAGACAGCUGCAGACAGCAAAAUGCGUCCAGUCCUUUGCUUAGUUUGUGGUCCCCAAAGGUGUCAGUCUGAGAGAAGAGGCAGGGUUUAGAGGAGAAGAGUUGUACCACUCAUCAGACUCUCCUUGCUGAGUGACGGUGAACACAUCUCUGGUGUUCUUUCAGGCCAUGGGAUGGGAGUCCUGUGAGAGUGAAGACAUCUGCAGCAGAAUUUAUGAGAGUGCACAAAGAAUUGAUUCUAUAACCUUCCUGCCCUCAAGUGGCUUCCACCUCAAGUGGAAGAUUCAGACUCGGAUUGCUAACGAAAAGUACCUAAGGACCCACAAAGAAGUAGAGUGGCUCAUAAGUGGUUUCUUCAGGAACAGUUUCCAGGAGCAGCCUGGGUAUCUGAGACUGGCUGCUGUGGGAACAGCCCCAGAUACUUCCUUUCCUUUCUUACCAUGUUCCUGUCAAGGCCAGAGAAAUAUUUUUGAAAAGACCAGACAACAUCCUAGAAUUUGCUGCAGACUACUUCACGGAUCCAAGACUUCCCAACAAGAUUCACAUGCAGCUAAUUAAAGACAAGAAAGCGGCUUAAUUAGCAAAAUCAUGAUGCUCAGCUGUUGGGAGAGACCAGACGGAAUCCAGCCUCGGGGGUCAUCUGGAGGCAUGAGAGCCCUACUGCCAUCAGUGUGGGUUUCCAAGCUGCCUUGGGCUCUGUCUACUGUCGCAAAAGCUUUUAAAGAUAUUCAUUAAACACGGACCUUCCUGCUCUCUCUGCUUUAUUUCACUCAAGAGGAGGAAGCCAUCCUUCAGGGGAGGGCUGCUGUGCCCCACUUUGACGUGUGAGGCAGCCGGCCUGUUUCUGCUUUCAGGGCGGCCAGGGGCCUCUUGCUGGGUCAGUGGGCUGUCGUGCCCACCCCCUGGGAAGAACACAGCUGAUCACGGGGGCACAGAAACAAGCAAGUCCAUG